AGUUGCUCUCCUGGAUGGCUUUAUGUCUCCGCGGUGUUUCCUAGAGUCUCGGCGUUUCUACCUCUUCGCACCCUUUCCUGCCACCCUUUGUCCCCUGGAAGCCCGGAGACAUCAGCGGCUGCAAUUUUGCUACUCGCUGCUCGGCGUGGAACUGUCAGGACAAAAAAUAAUAUCCAAAGAUAUUUUGGCACUAACGGCGCUAUCUGUAGCAAGAAAGUUGAGCAGUGUGAACUGUUGAGACUUCCAAGGAGACUUCAGACAACCAAGACAGUGUAAAGGAAAACAGAGAAAAAGACUUGUUAGACAUUAUUAAGGGCACGAAAGUUGAAUUGAGCACAGUAAAUGUACAAACAACAAAGCCACCCAACAGAAGUUCACUUAAAAGCUACAACUGGCGGGCCUCAAAGAGCUUUAGGACAUGCUCCAAAGAAGAGAAAUGAGCCCCUGAGUCCUGAGUUGGUGGCAGCUGCAUCUGCUGCUCUGUUUUGACAAGCAAACAAGCCAGAACUGCUCAGGCAGCUCCGUAGCAUGAGGAAGAGUCAGGGGCACAGAGAGAUGGAGAGAGACCUAGUUAGUUUCAAUAACAAAAUAUCAGAUAUGAAAAUUGCCAGAUGUGCUACAGCUAGAAUUAAUAUAAGGCCAGAGCAUCAGAUUCAGUUUGACCAAGGCUAUGACAAUUAUCCUGGCCUGGAGAAGACUGCUGAUCUUAGAAACAGGAAAAAUAUAUUCAGGGGGAAGAGAUGUAAUAGAUUUCACAUUAUGGCAGUUACUAAAGAAGCACGUGAACAGACACAUCACCUUCACUUUGGGAUAUGGAAUUUGAUAAGCAGUUAGCCACAGAAUAUGAACAACCCCUUGAGAAUGAGAUUGAAGAACUGAUCCAGGGGACAAAAGAGGGGAAACUGAGAGUUCCCAAUUAAUAAUGAAGCAGCUUCAUAUCUAAGAUCUCUGGUGGACUUUUUCUGCCCGUGGACGCCGCUGAAGAAGCAUCGUUAAAGUCUCUCUUCACCUUGCCGUCAUGUCUAAGUCAGCGUCUCCAAAAGAGCCCGAACAGCUGAGGAAGCUCUUCAUUGGAGGGUUGAGCUUUGAAACAACUGAUGAGAGCCUGAGGAGCCAUUUUGAGCAAUGGGGAACGCUCACAGACUGUGUGGUAAUGAGAGAUCCAAACACCAAGCGCUCCAGGGGCUUUGGGUUUGUCACAUAUGCCACUGUGGAGGAGGUGGAUGCAGCUAUGAAUACAACGCCACACAAGGUGGAUGGAAGAGUUGUGGAACCAAAGAGAGCUGUCUCCAGAGAAGAUUCUCAAAGACCAGGUGCCCACUUAACUGUGAAAAAGAUAUUUGUUGGUGGCAUUAAAGAAGACACUGAAGAACAUCACCUAAGAGAUUAUUUUGAACAGUAUGGAAAAAUUGAAGUAAUUGAAAUCAUGACUGACCGAGGCAGUGGCAAGAAAAGGGGCUUUGCCUUUGUAACCUUUGACGACCAUGACUCCGUGGAUAAGAUUGUCAUUCAGAAAUACCAUACUGUGAAGGGCCACAACUGUGAAGUUAGAAAAGCCCUGCCAAAGCAAGAGAUGGCUAGUGCUUCAUCCAGCCAAAGAGGUCGAAGGGGUUCUGGAAACUUUGGUGGUGGUCGUGGAGAUGGUUUCGGUGGGAAUGACAACUUUGGUCGUGGAGGAAACUUCAGUGGUCGUGGUGGCUUUGGUGGCAGCUGUGGUGGUGGUGGAUAUGGUGGCAGUGGGGAUGGCUAUAAUGGAUUUGGUAAUGAUGGAAGCAAUUUUGGAGGUGGUGGAAGCUACAAUGAUUUUGGCAAUUACAACAAUCAGUCUUCAAAUUUUGGACCCAUGAAGGGAGGAAAUUUUGGAGGCAGAAGCUCUGGCCCCUAUGGCGGUGGAGGCCAAUACUUUGCAAAACCACAAAACCAAGGUGGCUAUGGCGUUUCCAGCAGCAGCAGUAGCUAUGGCAGUGGCAGAAGAUUUUAAUUAGGAAACAAAGCUUAGCAGGAGAGGAGAGCCAGAGAAGUGACAGGGAAGCUACAGGUUACAACAGAUUUGUGAACUCAGCCAAGCACAGUGGUGGCAGGGCCUAGCUGCUACAAAGAAGACAUGUUUUAGACAAAUACUCAUGUGUAUGGGCAAAAAACUCGAGGACUGUAUUUGUGACUAAUUGUAUAACAGGUUAUUUUAGUUUCUGUUCUGUGGAAAGUGUAAAGCAUUCCAACAAAGUGUUUUAAUGUAGAUUUUUUUUUUUGCACCCAUGCUGUUGAUUGCUAAAUGUAAUAGUCUGAUUGUGACGCUGAA